AUUUAGGCGGUGACAGACAGCAUCCGCAGUCAAUAGGAAGAGCUGAAGAAUUCUUUAGGUCUCCCAAAAUGGCCUUUGCUCAGGCCAUGCCCUCCGCCCAGCACAUCUGCUCCUCCACCUGCACCUGACUCCCUGGCCCUCGUGAAGCCACUCCCAUACUCCUAGACAGGGCUGCUGCGCCCUCCACUUCUGGGCUCCUGACCAGCUCUGCCGGAGCCGCUGCCUUGCCCCCCGGAGACUGAAGACAUGGCACCCAAGAGGGCCAAGAGAAGGACAGUAGAGGGCGGAAGCUCCAGCGUCUUCUCCAUGUUCGACCAGACUCAGAUCCAGGAGUUCAAAGAGGCCUUCACUGUGAUCGACCAGAACCGUGAUGGUAUUAUAGACAAGGAGGACCUUCGGGACACCUUCGCAGCCAUGGGCCGCCUCAAUGUGAAGAAUGAGGAGUUGGAUGCCAUGAUGAAGGAAGCCAGCGGUCCCAUCAACUUCACCGUCUUCCUGACCAUGUUCGGGGAGAAGCUCAAGGGUGCCGACCCUGAGGAUGUGAUCACCGGAGCCUUCAAGGUCUUGGACCCUGAGGGAAAGGGCACCAUCAAGAAGAAGUUCCUGGAGGAGCUGCUGACCACGCAGUGUGACCGCUUCUCCCAGGAGGAGAUCAAGAACAUGUGGGCGGCCUUCCCCCCCGACGUGGGCGGCAACGUCGACUACAAAAACAUCUGCUACGUCAUCACGCACGGCGACGCCAAGGACCAGGAGUAGGGGCACCCGCGGGCCUCCGCUGCCCGACGCUUCUGUUCGGCCCGACCUCCACCCCGGCUCCCAAUAAAAUUUAACUGAUCUUUGUUUCUUA